GCGGGGAAGUGGCGGCUGAAGCGCCGCCGGCGGGGCUCACUGUGGUGGUGUGAGUGGGAGGCGGCGGCGCUGGUGGCUGCAGCUGGGGUGAGGCGCGAGGCGGCGCACUCGACGGCUGACUGGAGCAGCGGAUAUAAGUCAAAGAGUACAGCAGAAAAUGUCUACUGAACGGACUUCUUGGACAAGCCUGUCCACCAUUCAGAAAAUAGCCCUGGGCCUUGGGAUCCCAGCCAGUGCAACAGUUGCCUAUAUCCUAUACCGCAGGUAUAGGGAAAGCAGAGAAGAGCGGCUGACAUUUGUUGGGGAAGAUGACAUUGAGAUAGAGAUGCGGGUUCCCCAGGAGGCUGUGAAACUCAUCAUUGGCCGGCAAGGAGCCAAUAUUAAACAGCUGCGGAAACAGACAGGUGCUCGGAUUGAUGUGGACACAGAGGAUGUAGGCGAUGAGCGAGUGCUGCUUAUCAGUGGUUUUCCUGUUCAGGUGUGCAAGGCCAAAGCAGCAAUCCAUCAGAUCCUGACAGAGAAUACCCCAGUGUCUGAGCAGCUUUCAGUUCCCCAGAGAUCUGUGGGCAGAAUCAUAGGGAGAGGCGGCGAGACAAUUCGUUCUAUCUGUAAGGCAUCUGGAGCCAAAAUUACCUGUGACAAAGAAUCAGAAGGGACAUUACUACUAUCAAGACUUAUAAAAAUCUCAGGAACACAGAAGGAAGUGGCAGCAGCCAAGCAUUUGAUACUGGAGAAAGUUUCAGAAGAUGAAGAACUUCGGAAGAGAAUUGCUCAUUCUGCAGAAACCAGGGUCCCACGCAAACAGCCAAUCAGUGUGAGAAGAGAAGACAUGACAGAGCCAGGUGGAGCUGGAGAGCCAGCAUUAUGGAAAAACACCAGUUCUAGCAUGGAGCCGACUGCACCCCUGGUGACUCCUCCACCCAAAGGAGGAGGCGACAUGGCUGUGGUAGUGUCAAAGGAAGGUUCCUGGGAGAAACCUAGUGAUGACAGCUUUCAGAAGUCUGAAGCCCAGGCCAUCCCAGAGAUGCCCAUGUUUGAAAUCCCCAGUCCUGACUUCAGUUUUCAUGCUGAUGAGUACCUAGAAGUCUACGUUUCUGCUUCUGAGCACCCUAACCACUUCUGGAUCCAGAUCGUUGGCUCCCGCAGCCUGCAAUUGGAUAAGCUUGUCAAUGAGAUGACCCAGCACUAUGAGAAUAGUGUGCCUGAAGACUUGACUGUGCAUGUAGGAGACAUUGUAGCAGCACCUUUACCUACAAAUGGUUCCUGGUAUCGAGCCCGGGUCCUCGGCACCUUGGAGAAUGGGAACUUGGACCUCUAUUUUGUUGACUUUGGAGAUAAUGGAGAUUGCCCACUGAAGGACCUCAGGGCUCUCAGGAGUGACUUCCUAAGCCUUCCAUUUCAAGCAAUAGAAUGUAGUCUGGCACGGAUUGCUCCCUCAGGUGACCAGUGGGAAGAGGAAGCUUUGGAUGAGUUUGAUAGACUCACUCAUUGUGCUGACUGGAAGCCUCUGGUAGCCAAGAUCUCUAGCUAUGUCCAGACUGGGAUCUCAACUUGGCCAAAGAUCUACUUAUAUGAUACUAGCAAUGGGAAGAAACUUGAUAUUGGGCUAGAAUUAGUACACAAAGGAUACGCAAUUGAGCUUCCUGAAGACAUAGAAGAAAACAGAGCUGUCCCAGACAUGUUGAAGGACAUGGCCACAGAAACAGAUGCCUCUCUCAGCACGUUGCUCACUGAGACCAAAAAGAGCUCUGGAGAGAUAACACAUACCCUGUCCUGCCUCAGCUUAUCAGAAGCUGCUUCCAUGUCUGGUGAUGAUAACCUUGAAGAUGACUACUUACUCUGAAGUCUGGGCUUCAGUUUGCUCAGCCAUCUGCUUUGCUGUGUGCUCCAUAUGUUUGAGAUCCAUUUUGUCCUGCUGGCCACAUCCCUUGAAUGGAUUCUGUGUAAUUUCACCAGUGCUCCUUCAGUCUGGCCCCUAACACCACCUGCAGGGGCUUCCUCAGAGUCCAGUUGUAACUUGAUGGAACAAGUUACAACUUCCCACCUUCGUGGUAGGUGGGAAGAAAAGAAUCCCUGAAAUGCCUGAGGGUGCAUUUUUAAAGACAGGGGAAGAGGGUCUCCUAUAAAGGAAAAGGAGUUAUCCAGCUGCCUCAGCGCGAAAAGCAAGGAAGAACAGCAGAUCCCCACCUCUGUCGUUCCGAUCAUUCUGGAAGUUCACAAACACAGAGUCCACAUUUGUCUUCUCUUCCACGUACUCCAGGGUUGCAGUCAAACUAGGAGCCACAGAAAAACAGUUAAAAUGUUUGGCCGCUCCCUCUCCCUCUCCCUCUCCGUCUCCGUCUCCCCAUGGUCUCCCUCUCCCUCUCUCUCCACGGUCUCCCUCUGAUGCCACCAAAGUUGUGAAAGCCGAAGCUGGACUGUACUGCUGCCAUCUCGGCUCACUGCAACCUCCCUGCCUGAUUCUCCUGCCUCAGCCUGCUGAGUGCCUGGGAUUGCAGGCGCGUGCCGCCAUGCCUGACUGGUUUUCGUAUUUUGGUGGAGACGGGGUUUCGCUGUGUUGGCCGGGCUGGUCUCCAGCUCCUAACCACGAGUGAUCUGCCAGCCUCGGCCUCCUGAGGUGCCGGGAUUGCAGACGGAGCCUCGUUCACUCAGUGCUCAGUGUUGCCCAGGCUGGAGUGCAGUGGCGUGAUCUCGGCUCGCUACAACCUCCACCUCCCAGCCGCCUGCCUUGGCCUCCCAAAGUGCCGAGAUUGCAGCCUCUGCCCGGCCACCACCCCGUCUGGGAAGUGAGGAGCGUCUCUGCCUGGCCGCCCAUCGUCUGGGAUGUGAGGAGCGCCUCUGCCCGGCCGUCAUCCCGUCUAGGAAGUGAGGAGCGUCUCCGCCCAGCCGCCCAUCGUCUGGGAUGUGGGGAGCGCCUCUACCCGGCCACGACCCUGUCUGGGAACUGAGGAGUGUCUCUGCCCAGCCGCGACCCCAUCUGGGAGGUGAGGAGCAUCUCUGCCCGUCCGCCCUGUCUGAGAAGUGAGGAGCCCCUCCGCCCGGCAGCCGCCUCGUCUGGGAAGUGAGGGGCGUCUCCGCCCGGCAGCUGCCCCGUCCGGGAGGUGGGGGGCAGCCCCCGCCCGGUCAGCCGCCCCGUCUGGGAGGGAGGUGGGGGGCAGUCCCCACCCGGCCACCGCCCCCUCCGGGAGGUGGGGGGUGCGUCUGCCCGGCCGCCCCUUUUGGGAAGUGAGCCCCUCUGCCCGGCCGCCACACCGUCUGGGAGGUGUACCCAAGAGCUCAUUGAGAAUGGGCCAUGAUGACGAUGGCGGUUUUGUCGAAUAGAAAAGGGGGAAAUGUGGGGAAAAGAUAGAGAAAUCAGAUUGUUGCUGUGUCUGUGUAGAAAGAAGUAGACAUAGGAGACUCCAUUUUGUUCUGUACUAAGAAAAAUUCUUCUGCCUUGGGAUGCUGUUAAUCUAUAACCUUACCCCCAACCCCAUGCUCUCUGAAACGUGCUGUGUCCACUCAGGGUUAAAUGGAUUAAGGGCGGUGCAAGAUGUGCUUUGUUAAACAGAUGCUUGAAGGCAGCAUGCUCGUUAAGAGUCAUCACCACUCCCUAAUCUCAAGUACCCAGGGACACAAACACUGCGGAAGGCCGCAGGGUCCUCUGCCUAGGAAAACCAGAGACCCUUGUUCACUUGUUUAUCUGCUGACCUUCCCUCCACUAUUGUCCUAUGACCCUGCCAAAUCCCCCUCUGUGAGAAACACCCAAGAAUGAUCAAUAAAUACUGGGAAAAAAAAAUUUGGCCAACUCAGAAUCCAGAAAGACACCUACUUGGAGCAGUAAAAAUAUUAUUGGUCGUUUUCUGCCCUCCACCCACCCAAGCCAGGAAAUGAAAGUUGCUAAACUAGUUUUGGUAGAUUUUUCUUGGAAGCCAAGAGAUUGCACAUCACUGGAUGUAAGCCACAGAAGGGGUCUGGGGAGAAAGGACUACUGAGAUGAACAGCUAGAAAGUACUUCCCGUUAUUCAACUAUUUCUGGAUCUGAGUCCAGCUUCCCAUGGACUCUUAUCCCUUGAACCCCAGAUCCUGGCUCAGCUCACAGGCUUGUCUGCAUGCCAGGUGAAUGGAUUGCUUAUAUCUAGCUCCAGAAUUAGCCUUAUGUACUAUGACAUGAUAGAAGGGUGAAAUCCCCUACCUAUUCCCUCCCCAUUCUCCCAUCCAGGCUCAGUCACCUUUCCCGGUUGCCUUGAUCCAAGGCCUGAUAUGGGAUAUCCAGGAAGAGUCGACGGUCACAGAGAAGGCCGUGCCAAUGGGCAGAGGUCUGGGAGGUAAGGCGGAAGUGAAAGUCUAACUGUACUGGGUCCUGGUGGAGCAGGGGGUCAGUAGCCAGCACCGUCAAGUUCCCAGCCUGGAAAAGGAGUAAAAAUGCUCCUCUAGUCUUCAAAUCAGACCUCAGGCAGAUGGGGGUGUGUCCGUUGAAGCAAGGUGGGCAUUGAUGGGGAGAGCCUGGGAGAAUUGGAGCCAAGAUCUUAAAGAUGCAAUAAUAUCCCUUAGUCCCAGGAACUAAUAGCCUAUGCCUAUUGUGGAGUUCUCCUUUAUAUCAAACAAUCCAGCUGAGGCAGUAUUACUGCCUGUUGACUUCAACCCAGGAGUACAAUAACCAUUUAGGAACUUAGAAAUGUUUACAUCAGAGAGCUUAGGAUUUAAACAAAGCUUUAUAAUGUGCUUCCUUUCUCACUAAUAAUUUCCACUUUUUUCAUUAUAUGGGUUUUCUCUAAAUUCUUCUAUUUAAAAUGCCAUGGUUACAACCAGGCUUGUUAUUGCAAUAUGAUAUGUGGGCAAGUUCUGGAUUCCAGAUCCUGCUUAGCAUCUUUAAGCAGGAUCUUGGCAUAAACAGCUUUAUGUCCCAGAAGUCCUACAGAGUUUGUUUUACCUUUGUCCCCACUCCCUCUUUUCCCAAUCCUGAUUUUCACUACCAUCUGUAUGACCUUGAUUUUACAGUCUGUGGGCCAGAAUGCUUGUCUAUAUAGCAAGUAGCUUUUACACAUGCGUUCCAAGAUUCCAUCUACCUCUGUAAUUCAUCUUCCAACUUGCUAAUGUCCCUCCUCUGCAAGGUAUGCAAGAAAAGGGUUGCCCUGUCACAGCACUAGCUCACAGUCCACUUACCGAAUACAGUUCUUUAAGCUGGUCGUGGUUACCCUGCUCGGUGCUUUUGCCCUCCUGGAGGCCUACUAGGGACUCAGGAGCACUGGAGGCAGGAACGGGGCUGGAGUGUCAAGUCCUCCUCUUCCUUAUAAGUGAUGCUGGUUGGGAAAGAGACCCAAAUUAGUUUAUCUUGGAAUCUGAGGUGGGAAGAUACACAGUACCAGGCUCUGGCAUGAUCUUCUGUAUUUUCUGUUGUCCAGCCUGUUUCUAUGUUCCUGGGCCCAACCAGAUGGAAAAAUUCUAAAGUUCCAUGCCAGCUUUCCACCCCCUAUUCUGUUGUUAUUUCUUGCCAUUUGGGAAAUUCUUUCAAAUUCUUUUACUUUUUCCUUACAUUUUAUAUAAACAACUACAAAUAGAGAUGAAAACAAGUACCUUUUAUAACAACGAGGCAGCAUCUUCUCCCGGAGAGUGAUCCGGUACUUGUAACAGUAAAGGUAAUAGGCGUAUGGUGACCAGAUCGGGUAGAGGUAGUUACGUGUUUUUCCCCUCUUGAUAUAAGAAAGGGAGUAGACAGAGGGGCGACACCUCUUACAAGGCAGUUUUUCAGUUCAGUGCCUCCCUGUGGCAAAGUGAAGUUCACAGGUGGGUGGCAGAGGUUUAGGCAACCUGGUGGCAUUGUGACCCAGUGGGCACUAUGACAUGGAUAAGGGGUCAGCCCUUAUGUCACCUCAGGACUCCACUCUGCUGCUUAUCUACCCUAAUCCCUUAUCCAAGGCUCAUAUUCGACUAGUAUGCAUGUUAUGGCUGUAUGAAUGAUUAAAAAAUAGAACUUGAA